AGAGGCAGCGGUUGGAGGCGCGGUGGGUGUCUGCGGGGGUCUCGCGGGGCGGCUGCGGUGUUUCACCGGGAAAGGCUCGAGGAGAGCGCGGCUCACGAGAGAUAACCCAGCUGUGCUCCCUGGAACCUUCAAUUUCAAGGCCUCCCUGCCUCUACUAGGCGCCUUAGCUCACUAUGGGGAACCACUUGACUGAGAUGGCGCCCACUGCCUCCUCCUUCUUGCCCCACUUCCAAGCCCUGCAUGUCGUGGUCAUUGGGCUGGACUCUGCUGGAAAGACCUCCCUCCUUUACCGCCUCAAGUUCAAGGAGUUUGUCCAGAGUGUCCCCACCAAAGGCUUCAACACCGAGAAGAUCCGGGUGCCCCUCGGGGGAUCGCGUGGCAUCACCUUCCAAGUGUGGGACGUCGGGGGGCAGGAGAAGCUGCGACCACUGUGGCGCUCUUAUACCCGCCGGACAGACGGUCUAGUGUUUGUGGUGGACGCUGCGGAGGCUGAGCGGCUGGAGGAAGCCAAGGUGGAGUUGCACCGAAUCAGCCGGGCCUCGGACAACCAGGGCGUGCCAGUGCUGGUGCUGGCCAACAAGCAGGACCAGCCCGGGGCACUGAGCGCUGCUGAGGUGGAGAAGAGGCUGGCAGUCCGAGAGCUAGCAGCCGCCACUCUCACUCAUGUGCAAGGCUGCAGCGCUGUGGACGGUCUGGGCCUGCAGCAGGGCCUUGAGCGCCUCUAUGAGAUGAUCCUCAAGAGGAAGAAGGCAGCUCGGGGUGGCAAGAAGAGACGGUGACCCAAGCCCCCCCUCCCUUUCCUCCCACCUAGUAGGGGUCUGCACACUUGGACAGCAGGGUGGGACCAGCCUGUGACCUCUCAGUCAGACUGGGGUGCAGGACCUGUCCACCUCAAUGAAGGAGAGAGGAGCAUGGGGUGUCCCGUUUUGGUGCCACACUGGGGUGGGGAUGGGAGAUGGGAUGUCUUUGCAUAUCUCUCUCAUCCUCUCUGGAGAAGUGGGCGCUGCAGGACUGUGGAGACGUAAAUGUAAACUGUGACUCUACCUCGACCCUGUUUCUUAUUUUUCUUCUCUGGCUAAAAAUUUUUAAUUGGAUGUGUUUGGGGGCGGGGGGAUGGAAGUGACUUGGAGAAUGUGUUUGGGAUGAAAUAACUAUCUCCCCUUCCUCUGUCCCCCAACUGGGGAGUCUCCCCAGGCUGCUUUUCUAGGAAUACCAGUCACAUAGUUUUUAUUUUUGUGUCUGUGAAAGUGCCAAGAACCCCUCCCCACAUUUGUAGAUCCAUGACCCUUUUUAUAAGCUGUGUGUGUCCUCUGUAUUAUUGUUAUUAACUAUUUUUUAGCAUUUGCCUGUAAGUUAUUAAAGACUGAUAACUGUAGCUCUUACCUUGGUCUGGGGCAUUUUCCUCUCCUUAUCUUGCCCCAGAGACAAUUCAAGAUUUCUAUAUGGGGUUGUGGCGCAGGGGGAGGGAGAUUUAUCUUGAAGCUGAAUUUGCAAAGCAAGCACUUAUAAAAAUUAGAUUGUGUGUUACGGGAUGGCUUGUGAAAAUUAUAGGGGGGAGUGGAAAACCCCUCAAGCUAU